AAGUGCCUGGAUUAUAGACAUGAGCCACCGUGCCUGGCCUAAGAGUCCAGAAAUGCCUAAUUUUUCUUUAGUGCCUUUUAGUUGCCUCUUUUUUUAUUAAUAUAAAAAAUACCAGAAACACUGAGAAAAUAAAAAGAAAUAAAACCCUAGAAGUUACUAGGAAGAAAAAAAAAAAGUGAAUGGCACGGAAGAUGAGCAAGCAGAUAGUGAAAUGCCUGAAGUGGACAUGGUGAGGGAGGGAGGAAACUAUGAUACUGGGUGAAGCACAGAGUGAAUCUUGUGAAAUGGUGAUGUGAAAAGCAGCCUCCUUUAGUGAUGUCCUAUUCUUGCUCUAUCACAUUUUAGUGCUUCAUGGGCCAUAAGGAGGCUUGGAGGCAAGGAAGUUACCAGCAUUGUUGGAUACCACGUUUUGCCUGUCUGAAGGCCUCGUCCCUUACAUGUCCGUAUAGACAUGUUUCUCUGUCUUUUGAGGUUGGGUGGAUUAAGUAGGCCAGAUGGUGUGUCAAAGGUGGCAACAAGGCUGUAGUAGCACUGGACACUCAGGAAUGCCAGGAACACAGUCCCCCAGAUUUAACAGUUUCUGAGAAUAAAGCACAGUUCCUGGACAAUGAAAGAUUUCUUUGAAGCAAAAUUUCUGGUAAGGAGAUGGACAUUCACAAAGAUCAGAAUUCAUAGCACAUUUCAAUAUCUGCAGACCUACAGAUCUAUGCAAGGCUCUCCCUGGGAAUGGAAAGAACUCACUGACAGUUCCUUAUUUUCGAGAACAUGGGUGGCAGCAGGGGUGCCCUGGGUGCCUUGCAGAGCAGUGUGGCUCACUCUACACAGACACAAAGCCUCUGAGUUUCAGCUCCCACUUCCCUUGUAGGUAACCAGAACUUGCAUCCUCACCUUUAGAGAGUCAGCAGCAAUGGUGAACUCCUCAAGUGAGGAGAGAAAGGAUAGCUCAAAUCCAGAAGCCUGCUCUUUGGUGAAAAAUGAUGUCUUUGAUGAGUGAGGCUGCAGAUCUAACUUUACUUGAAACUGCCUAAAAAAUAUAUAUAUACAUUUUUUUUUGCUAUUAAAAAAACCAUAGAAAACCCAAGAGAGUCCUUUCAAACUUCAGAAAUAGGAUGUACAGAGGAGGAGGACUGUGAGAGAGAGUUCGAAUAUGAACAAAGCAGGGGGCAAUUUUUAUAUGUUACUUAGGCAUAUAACCUUCUGCAGUGAAUUUCUUUAGAGUUGAUAUUUCUUUUUUAUUGUUUCCCACACUGCUUCAGAUAUUUUCAGACAGAUUUUUUUGGUUUUGGUUUUUUAGCUACACUGAGCUCGUCCUUAAUGUGGGAGCUGCCAUCCCAGAAUCUUUUCUCAAUAUAUUUUGGAUGAACUGCUGCUUGAGUUUCCCUGAGUGAGUGAUUAAAGUGACUGUUCCUAUUUGUUUUCUGCAAACACAACAAACUAUAAUUCGUUCUAAGGAGAGCUCAAAGGCAGGAAGCCAUUUGUCUGCUGACAACCUUUUCUCAGAACAACCUGUGAUGCCUCUUCUAGCUGGGGCUGGACAUCCAUCCUGGCUCCCAACUGGUGUCCUUGAGGUGGGGCCUAUGGGGCUGGACUUAAAGCAUAGUUCUCUUGAUUAGAAGCUGCCGUCUGUCCUGCUGGGCCUCUGGAGUCUGCCUUUAGUAGUGCUGUGUCACAGGAAUAGUCCCAGACUGAGACACAGAACCUGGAAUUUAGCCAGUGACAAGCCGUGCUAGCUUUCAAAGGUCGCUGUGUGGGCCUCGGUGUCUUCCUUAGUUAAAUGGGUGCACUGGAUGCUAUAAUCUCUAGGUUUCACUCUGACACUAAGAAUUUGUGAUUUUUUCUUCUGAUUCCUGGUCCAAGGGUUCCUUCUCUCCUGGAGAUGGAGACACCAUGACCACUCUCAUGGAUCUUUUCUUCUUGGAAGAAGGGGUGAAUAUAGAGAAUGACAAAGAAAAAGUGAGAUGACAGUGAUCAGUGUUAUGAAGAACAUGGCUUGGGUAGGGCUGGUUCCUUGUAUUGAGUGGUCAAGAAUCAAGAAGGUGAAUCUGCAGUCCCAUCUGUUCAAGGUGCAGCAGAAAGAAGUGAAGCCAGGGAUGGAGCGGGGAGCAAGGAGGAAUGAGCGGCCACAUCAGAGGGACCAGGCCUGCGAACUUGAGCAGGGUGAGGCAUCCAGGGCUCCUGGUUCCUGGCACGGCAUCCUCCUAGUCCUCUAACCAGGGAGUUUCCUGCUCUGCCCUUGAUAUGAAUGAAUGAAGGCAGUCACCGGCAGCAUUGAUUCUCUGUCAAUAAUUCUCCCCCUCCUCCCUCAUCCCCAAGGCUCAGCUCAGACGCAAUUUCUUUCUCUCUUUUUUUGCACAAUGGCUUUACUGAAAUAUAAUUCACCAACUAUAAAAGUCAUUCUUUUUUCAAAGGACAACUUUAUGGUUGGUGAACCACAAUUCAGUGGUUUUUAGUGUAGUCACAGAGUGAUAGACAAAAUUUCUUCUUUUUGUAGGUGGAAGAAGGAACAAAUUAUAAAUUGUGUGAUUUCAGAUGUCUGGACUUUUCAUUCUUUUAUUUUAAAAUAUGUCUAUUUACCAUGUUUGCUUUGUUUUUUUUUUUCCUUCCUGCCUCUGUUACUGCUAUUACUGUGUUCCAUUUUUCCUUCUCAUAAUUUGCAAGCCAUACAUGCAACUUUGGUUCACUAAUUGAUUGCUCUUAAGUUUUCAUCAAGAAGUUAUAUUCAUUUUUAUUUCUCUACACUUAAACAGUACCUUUAACCUCCUCCCCACCAAAAAAUACUGAGAUAUUCACAUACAAUUUCUCUCUUUUAUUUCCCUCACUGCCACCAUGUGGAAACCAAUGGGUGUUUUAAUUUGGUAUGAACAUGAGCAUUUUAGGUUUAAAAUGUGUUUCACUGCAUUUUGACUGUAGGAAGUGAGAUCAAAGGACAGAGAGCGGGGAGGAGGGAUCACAUCCUGUAAGGCCUUUCAGACCAUUUCCAAAUCUUGAUUUGAUUCUGAGAAAGGUGAGAAGCCAUUGGAGGAUUGAGAUAAGAAGAAUGACAUCUUCUAAUUUACAUUCUGAAAGAUUACUCUGGUUGCUGAGUUGGGAAUAGGGGAGUUAGGAGUAAAAAAUGGGAGAAUUCAUGGGCUUGCUGUAAUAAUCCCAUUAAGAGUUAAUGUGGCUGAAUCCCAGUUGUUGCAAUUUAGGCAAUGAAGAGUUGACCAACUCUAUGUUUAUUUUAUGUAAUUUUUCAUAAUUUUUAAAUUUAGAAAUAAUUUUACACAAAACAUUUACAAUGUUAGAAGAAUGAUAAAGAGCUCCAAUAUAACCUUCACCCAGAUUCCCCAAUUGUAAUCUUUUCCACAUUGGUUUUUCUCUUUUUGUAUAUCCAUAUUGUAAUUUUUUGGAUUGAUUUGAUAAUAAAUAGAAAGCAUGCUGCCUUUAUCCUUAUAGUAUGUGGUGUAUAUUAUAUAAGAACAGGAUAUUCUCUUAUACAACCACAUACAAUGGUCAAGAUCAGGAAAAUAACAUUGAUACAAUUCUAUUAUUUAAUCUGCAGACUGUGUUAAUAUUUGGCCAAUUAUACCAGUAAUAUCCUUUAUAGAAAAAAUCUGGCCCAUGGACUCUAUGUGGACUAAUAUGAGAGACAGGGGAUAGGAGUUGCUGAAGGAGUGGAGGUGAAUUAUGGGAGAAAAAGAGGAAUUAGGGAUAAUUGUAAGAUUUUUCACGUAUGCAAAUAGAAAAUGGAGUUCGUAUUACUAGUUAAACUGCGAGGACUUUGCAAGGAAGAAGUUUUUGUGUAUGUCUGGGGCACAGUUCAGCCUUGGAUAUACUAAGUUUGAGAUGUUUAUUAUACAUCGAAGUGGAUAUGCUAAUUUGUUCUUUGUGAUUUGAAAUAACAUCUUUAUGUGUCUAAAUCUGAGUCUUUUCUAGUAGUUUAGCUCAGUGCUGGGUGGGACCUUUCAACAUAAACAUUUUAUCUUUUCUAUGUGUAGAAAAUGUCCUUUAAUUAUUUAUCUGAGCAUUUCAUUCUCUUUUGCUGUCUCCAGAUGAUGUUGGAACUUCUAUUAAUAGUUUUGUUCUUGGGGUUUUUUAGCUUUUCUUUUAAAUCUUCCAUCUCUUGACCUUUUUUGCUUCUAUCUGUGGGAGUAUUCUCAACCUUCUUACAAGCUCAUUGAUUGUGUGGUUUGGUACAUUUUAAUUAAAAUAACAACUCUGAGUCUUAUUUCACACCAUUCUCUUCUCUCUGAGGACAUUUUAAAGUUACUUUUUUCCACUUUGCCCUCUUAGCAAACCAACCCAUCUGUUAGUUCUUUUGUCUGGGAAAUUUGGUAUCCAUCUAAUGUGUCAUUAGCUCUCCUAAAAUAUCCAGUGACUGUUCUUUGUCUUUUUACUGUUGAAUGUGGAUGAAGUUACCUGAAGCAUGUACUUUUCUUUUCCAAGCCCAGACUCUUCAAUUUUUGUUUAAUUUGGGGGCAAGCUCUCCUAGGUGGGUGUCAUCUUGCUCCAAUCCUUAUAAUAUUUAAACUUGAAUAACCCUUUGCCAACUAUCCAAUCUGUUGCCAAAACAAGCUUUCAAAAUUGAAAUAUUAAGAUGUCAUUUAGUAUUCUAAAAUUCCCUGCAUCCCUCAUAAUUUUCAGAAUAAAAUUGAAAAUCCUUAGAGUGGCAACAUGCCGUAAAUAUGGGAAUCCUCAUGUACAGAUUCUCACCCACGUUCUCCUAAUAUGUCAAAUGUUCCAGGUACAUCAAACUAUUGGUAAUUCCCCGAAUGUGCAUCCAAGCCUUUGCCCAGAAUCUUCUCUUUCCCUGGAGUGCUUUAUUUCCUCCUCUCUACAUCUAGAACUUCAAUGCACCCUUCAAGAUCCAGUAACUGCUACAUAUCUGUACCCAAGCAUCUUUUACUUUAUUUUGAUGCCUUCAUCCUCAAGUACCUCUUAAAUAAUUACUGCUCUUUCUGAAUUCUUGCAGCAUUUUUCACGUACCCAUAGGUGUUUCUGUAAAUAAUUGAUGUGCCUCUUUCUCUCCUACCAAACAGGAGAUUUAAAAGCGGUGAUGUGUUUUAUUCAUUUCAGAAUCUUUGCUACCUACUGUACAGUAGACAGUUAGAGUGAUAUCACUUGUUUAAUAAAUUAAGUGAGAAAUCCCAAAGUAGGUUAUACUUGUUUGUCUGUUUUAAAAUGGUGCAGGGAGGGGUUCUGGUGACUAAGGUCUACACGCUAAUGAGCAUUUGGAUUAUUUAAUGUUAUUUUUCAGGGUUCUAUAAAUUGUGUAGGACUCUCAUUUUGUAGGCUGGUCUCUGAUGUUGGCUCUACCAUAGGUUUCUUAUAAAACAGCCACAGAAACCACUUCCAUAUCUCACUUUUGACAUUGAUGUAGUCCUCAGGCCAUGGACAAUGACCACUGAGACCCAAGCAAGGUUGUGGGCAAGGCUUUGGGAAGGGGGUUGAUAAGAUACAAGGGAAUAGCCACCAGCCAGGCCUCAGGAAGACCUGAGGAGCUCUCUUGUGUGUGGGAUGAGAUCAGACCAGAAUCACAAGAGAAUCAUGCAGGCAGGAUGGGAGAAUCCUGGUGCACCAGGAUAGGGCAGAGGCUUGUUUAGAGCUACAAAUACCAGCAAGGCCUGGCCUGGUAUGUCAGGUCAGCUAAUAUGUCAGUUCCCACAGCUCCCAUAGACAAUGGGAUGCCAGGGAAAGUUUUUAAAAAGAGAAGUGAAAUCAUUGAUGAUGCAAUUUGGACUUCAUUCUAGUUGUUUAGCUGUACAUUUGGGUCCUAGAGAAACAAGAAGCAAGCUGGAGGUAUGAAAGAGAACAUUCCAAGAAUGACAGGUUUUCCUGGGAUCAGCUGCACUCCUUAGCAAAAGUAUAUUGGAGAAUCAACUGAGAAAGUAACUGAGACAUUUCAAUCAUUUCUAGGUGUAAAGAAAGACCAGAUCCCAGGAAAAUAUUACGGUGACUUCCCAAGUAUGCCUGGCCACAAUACCUCCAGGAAUUCCUCUUGCGAUCCUAUAGUGACACCCCACUUAAUCAGCCUCUACUUCAUAGUGCUUAUUGGCGGGCUGGUGGGUGUCAUUUCCAUUCUUUUCCUCCUGGUGAAAAUGAACACCCGGUCAGUGACCACCAUGGCGGUCAUUAACUUGGUGGUGGUCCACAGCGUUUUUCUGCUGACAGUGCCAUUUCGCUUGACCUACCUCAUCAAGAAGACUUGGAUGUUUGGGCUGCCCUUCUGCAAAUUUGUGAGUGCCAUGCUGCACAUCCACAUGUACCUCACGUUCCUAUUCUAUGUGGUGAUCCUGGUCACCAGAUACCUCAUCUUCUUCAAGUGCAAAGACAAAGUGGAAUUCUACAGAAAACUGCAUGCUGUGGCUGCCAGUGCUGGCAUGUGGACGCUGGUGAUUGUCAUUGUGGUACCCCUGGUUGUCUCCCGGUAUGGAAUCCAUGAGGAAUACAAUGAGGAGCACUGUUUUAAAUUUCACAAAGAGCUUGCUUACACAUAUGUGAAAAUCAUCAACUAUAUGAUAGUCAUUUUUGUCAUAGCCGUUGCUGUGAUUCUGUUGGUCUUCCAGGUCUUCAUCAUUAUGUUGAUGGUGCAGAAGCUACGCCACUCUUUACUAUCCCACCAGGAGUUCUGGGCUCAGCUGAAAAACCUAUUUUUUAUAGGGGUCAUCCUUGUUUGUUUCCUUCCCUACCAGUUCUUUAGGAUCUAUUACUUGAAUGUUGUGACGCAUUCCAAUGCCUGUAACAGCAAGGUUGCAUUUUAUAACGAAAUCUUCUUGAGUGUAACAGCAAUUAGCUGCUAUGAUUUGCUUCUCUUUGUCUUUGGGGGAAGCCAUUGGUUUAAGCAAAAGAUAAUUGGCUUAUGGAAUUGUGUUUUGUGCCGUUAGCCACAAACUACAGUAUUCAUAUUUGCUUCCUUUAUAUUGGGAAUAAAAAUGGGUAUAGGGGAGGUAAGAAUGGUAUUUCAUUACUUGAUCAAAACCAUGCCUUGAUGUACCCAAAACAAAAGGACUAUAAAAUGCAAGAGCCCUCAUUGUAGUCCUUAUGGGAUCCCUCCCAUCUCUGAGUGAUGGCCGUACAAAGACCAGUGUUGUUGAAUCCACCUGGAGUUGCAAUAUUACAUUAUUUUCCAGUACAGAAUGUCUGUGUGGCCCAUGAAAGCAACAUAGGUUUUAAGAGUUUUAGAGUUUCAUUAGCUCAUUCUAAGUUCCUCUGUUUGAAGCAUGGUCUCUUAGGUUUUGGACUGAACUCAGACCUUUAGUUCUUUUCAUCCCACUUCACCUUAGGUAAGUAAAUUCUGGCCACCACCCAGCUCCAAAGACACAAACUCUCCUUCGCUAACCAGGUUAGAUGUCCCAUUCAUCUCAUGCCCUGAUAAAAACUGAUAAGGGGAGAGAAUAGUUAAAAAUUUUUCUAGGGUAUCAUAACUCUGGUAGGAAGUCAUCUGUCUAGAAAUCAAGAGAAAAAGAACGUGUGGCCUCCUGUUAUAACAAGGGUUUCUAGAUUUGUCCUGUGAAAGGUCGUUUAAGGACUUGGGGAUCAACUUCCUCAAUUAUCACCAAUUGCACUGUUGCUCCAAAAAUCAUUUAAAAGCUUACUGGACAUAUCUACAUAAUGGUGAAACUGUAAUUUAGAGACUAUCCCUGACUAAUGUGCUGGUAGGCAUUAAAAUGAGUUCCCAAGGGAAGUGAUUAAAAUUUUUUUCUCUUCUGUUUUUUGAGAGAAUUUCUAGAUGUCCUGGGCCACAGUUAAUUAAGAUUUUUAGGGGGGACAGAAAGUUAUACUGAAAUCUUUAGAGCUCCCUUCCGCCGUUAAAAUUAUAUAUAUAUAUAUUUAAAUUAUACCUUAAGUUCUGGGGUACAUGUGCAGAAUGUGCAGGUUUGUUACAUAGGUAUACACGUGCCAUGGUGGUUUGCGGCACCUGUCAACCCAUCUACAUUAGGUAUUUCUCCUAAUGCUCUCCCUCCCCUAGCCCCCCACCCCUGGACAGGCCCCAUUGUGUGAUGUUCCCCUCCCUGUGUCCAUGUGUUUUCAUUGUUCAACUCCCACUUCUAAGUGAGAACAUGCGGUGUUUGGUUUUCUGUUCCUGUGUUAGUUUGCUGAGAAUGAUGGUUUCCAGGUUAAAAUUAUAUAUUUUUAAAUAAAUGAAAACUGUGUUUUUAAAAGAGGACUUUUGAGAAGUAUAUAGAAAAACCAUUAAUUUAGACUCUGUGAGAUUAGGUUGCAUGAAGAAGGUUUUCUGAAUAUUUGAAGAGUGGAUAAAUAAAUGUCCCCCAAAGCAAUAAAAUCAUAAUCCUUUAAAAUAUAGGAAAAAUAACUAAUGGGAACUAGGCUUAAUACUCGGGAUGAAAUAAUCUGUACAACAAACUCCCAUGACACAUGUUUACCUAUGUAACAAACCUGCACAUGUACCCCUGAACUUAAAAUAAAAUUUAAAGUAAUAAUAAUAAAAUAAUAUGGAUUUUCUUUCCAAAUUCGGAAUUACUUUUUGUAAAAUUGUAUUAAUAACUUGUGGCAUGUGGCACGUUAAACUGAUUUUAUUUCAAGAACUUCUGUUACUGGCUAGGUUGAUACAUAGGCUUGUGGGUUUUUGCUUUUUGGGUUUUUUUUGCUCCUGCCCAUACUUCCAGUGUCUUCAGUGUUUUAUCUUAAAAUUUUCCCAGGAUCUGAUCCAGUUUCAUAUUUAAUGCUGCAGAAAACCUGAAGUGAUUAGUAACAUGAAUAGAAUAACAGAAUGAAUUAAGGGAACUUUUUUUUUCAUCAAGGUAUAUCUUCGGGAUUUAAAAGUUUUUCAUAAUUUAUUAUCACUGUGGAUCCACAAAUUCCUCAGAUGAAUAAGAAAUACCUCUGUGAAUUUCUGUGACCACUAAAAUUACUGAGCCACAGAAAUUAAUUCUGAGGAAGCAGAAGUAGCAACAUAGUUCAAACAUGACUUGUUUCCAUAUAUUUUCUGUUUUAUAUAUUCUUUUAAAUAUCCUUUUAAACAAGUAAUAUUUCUUUUCUUUCUUGCCUUUUUUCCCAUUUAUUUUUUACAUUUUUUCUUUCUCAUUUUGAACCAUAAAAUUUGUAAGACCGUUACUAAGACCCCUGAUAGUUUUAAGAAAAUUUAUAAUACCUAUAAAUAUGUAAAAAAAAUUUAGAAAAAUAUUUAAAUUAAAAGUAUUCAUGAGAAUUUCAUUACCUUGUAGAUUAUGUCAUACUCUUUUCCAGAUUUUAGAUAUGUUGAGGUCAGGCAAUUCAAAAGAAUUAAUCUCUGUAUUAAUCUGUUAUAAUGUUAACAUAACACUAUGUUAUUUUCAUAUAUUAUAAUAACAGGCUUAUUAGAAAUGUUCUCAAAAGAUAGAAAUGCAAUAUUUCAUAAUAUAAAAUAUCUUUUUCAUCAGUAUUUAUGGAAUAAAUAGAAAAAUUUUA